GACGCCCCAACAGAGCUGGGCAUCUGGGGGAAGUGGAGCAGCCGGGAAGAAAGGGUAGAGGCUUGGAGGAGGAAAGCUCAGUGAUUCCUUAGAUGACCAGAGAAAGUGAAAUUGAUUGAGCACCUACUAUGUGCCGGGAUCGUCUGGCAACUUUGCAUACCUAGAGAGAAUUAAAUUCGUUGAGCACCUACUGUAUGUGUCAAACUGAGUGCUAUACCCUUGACUUAAUCCCAGGAAAGAAAGAUUUAUUGAGCUUCUACUAUGUGCUAGUUUUGGUGCCACAGGCUUUGCAUUUAAAGAGCUAGAGUAAUAGCCCAUUUAAAUAGGAGGAAACGGGGGCUCAGGGAAGACGAGUCAACUACCACAAACACUCCUGUCCCUCUUCUGGAGCUGGCUGCAGCCUGCAUUACCUGGAGGUGGGGAAGGAAGAUUAAGAAGCUCCUUCGUUAUCCAGAGUUCUUGAGCUUUUUCUGGGUUGGUGCAGAGUGAGUUUCCUGGAUGAUUCCCUUCCCAGGAGGGGUUUCCUGUAACUUAGCUGUCUUGGAGGGCCCGGAAGGCAGCUCUGGAGGCCUCUCUGUGCCCUCCCCUCCCCUUGUCCCCAGCACCAGGAGGAUGACAGGGGAUGUUGUCCAAGACCUCAUGGAAGGUGGGAAGCCAGGCUGGGAGGGAGCAGCCAGGUCAGGAGCCAGUGAAUCAAGCCUCCUGUGGUGUCAGAGACAAGAUGGGGUCCCUGCAAGACCUGCGCCUGCAUUCCAGUCCAGCCUCACCAGGCUGCUCUAGGCAGCCCCACGACUGCCAAGAUAAAGUGCCACGAAGAAAAGAACCCAGCAUGUGUUCAGGUUUGCUGCGGGUCAAGAGCUGGGUCAGCCUCCAGACUUAUUGGAAACCCAGGGCCACACAGGGGGUUUAUGUCUUACCAUUAACAGAGGAAUAACCUGAGCCCCAGGAAGCCAAGUCAUUUGCCCAGGGCUGCCGGGCUGGUGAGAGGCAGAGUUGGCCUGCCAGAAGUGGAUGCCUGCCUACCUUCUACCACCUGAGCUGCCAAGGGUGGUGGGGUUGGCUUUGCCAAGCUCCCGGACUCUCAGAGUGGCAGCUGGAAGCCAGUGAUGGCAAUCCCCGAGCCAUGAUGAAGACUUUGUCCAGCGGGAACUGCACGCUCAGUGUGCCCGCCAAAAACUCAUACCGCAUGGUGGUGCUGGGUGCCUCUCGGGUGGGCAAGAGCUCCAUCGUGUCUCGCUUCCUCAAUGGCCGCUUUGAGGACCAGUACACACCCACCAUCGAGGACUUCCACCGUAAGGUAUACAACAUCCGCGGCGACAUGUACCAGCUCGACAUCCUGGAUACCUCUGGCAACCACCCCUUCCCCGCCAUGCGCAGGCUGUCCAUCCUCACAGGGGAUGUCUUCAUCCUGGUGUUCAGCCUGGAUAACCGGGAGUCCUUCGAUGAGGUCAAGCGCCUUCAGAAGCAGAUCCUGGAGGUCAAGUCCUGCCUGAAGAACAAGACCAAGGAGGCGGCGGAGCUGCCCAUGGUCAUCUGUGGCAACAAGAACGACCACGGCGAGCUGUGCCGCCAGGUGCCCACCACCGAGGCCGAGCUGCUGGUGUCGGGCGACGAGAACUGCGCCUACUUCGAGGUGUCGGCCAAGAAGAACACCAACGUGGACGAGAUGUUCUACGUGCUCUUCAGCAUGGCCAAGCUGCCACACGAGAUGAGCCCCGCCCUGCAUCGCAAGAUCUCCGUGCAGUACGGUGACGCCUUCCACCCCAGGCCCUUCUGCAUGCGCCGCGUCAAGGAGAUGGACGCCUAUGGCAUGGUCUCGCCCUUCGCCCGCCGCCCCAGCGUCAACAGUGACCUCAAGUACAUCAAGGCCAAGGUCCUUCGGGAAGGCCAGGCCCGUGAGAGGGACAAGUGCACCAUCCAGUGAGCGAGGGAUGCUGGGGCGGGGCUUGGCCAGUGCCUUCAGGGAGGUGGCCCCAGAUGCCCACUGUGCGCAUCUCCCCACCGAGGCCCCGGCAGCAGUCUUGUUCACAGACCUUAGGCACCAGACUGGAGGCCCCCGGGCGCUGGCCUCCGCACAUUCGUCUGCCUUCUCACAGCUUUCCUGAGUCCGCUUGUCCACAGCUCCUUGGUGGUUUCAUCUCCUCUGUGGGAGGACACAUCUCUGCAGCCUCAAGAGUUAGGCAGAGACUCAAGUUACACCUUCCUCUCCUGGGGUUGGAAGAAAUGUUGAUGCCAGAGGGGUGAGGAUUGCUGCGUCAUAUGGAGCCUCCUGGGACAAGCCUCAGGAUGAAAAGGACACAGAAGGCCAGAUGAGAAAGGUCUCCUCUCUCCUGGCAUAACACCCAGCUUGGUUUGGGUGGCAGCUGGGAGAACUUCUCUCCCAGCCCUGCAACUCUUACGCUCUGGUUCAGCUGCCUCUGCACCCCCUCCCACCCCCAGCACACACACAAGUUGGCCCCCAGCUGCGCCUGACAUUGAGCCAGUGGACUCUGUGUCUGAAGGGGGCGUGGCCACACCUCCUAGACCACGCCCACCACUUAGACCACGCCCACCUCCUGACCGCGUUCCUCAGCCUCCUCUCCUAGGUCCCUCCGCCCGACAGUUGUGCUUUGUUGUGGUUGCAGCUGUUUUCGUGUCAUGUAUAGUAGUAGAAAUGGAAAUCAUUGUACUGUAAAAGCCUAGUGACUCCCUCCUUGGCCAGGCCCUCACCCAGUUCAGAUCCACGGCCUCCACCCGGGACGCCUUCCUCCUCUGCUCCCAAACAGGGUUUCCGUGGCCUGUUUGCAGCUAGACAUUGACCUCCGCCAUUGAGCUCCACGGUUUACAGACAAUUGCACAAGCGUGGGGUGGGCAGGCCAGGACUGCUUUUUUUUAAUGCUCCCAUUUCACAGAGGAUACCACCGAGACUCGGAGGGGACACGAUGAGCACCAGGCCCCACCUUUGUCCCCUAGCAAAUUCAGGGUACAGCUCCACCUAGAACCAGGCUGCCCUCUACUGUGCUCGUUCCUCAAGCAUUUAUUAAGCACCUACUGGGUGCUGGGUUCACUGUGUCCUAGGAAACCAAGAGGGUCCCCAGUCCUGGCCUCUGCCCGCCCCUGCUGCCCCACCACCUUCUGCACACACAGCGGUGGGGAGGCGGGGAGGAGCAGCUGGGACCCAGAACUGAGCCUGGGAGGGAUCCGACAGAAAAGCUCAGGGCGGGUCUUCUCCUUGUGCCCGGGAUUGGGCUAUGCUGGGUACCACCAUGUACUCAGGCAUGGUGGGUUUUGAACCCAUAAACCAAAGGCCCUUGUCAUCAGCUCUUAACAAGUAUAUUUUGUAUUUUAAUCUCUCUAAACAUAUUGAAGUUUUAGGGCCCUAAGGAACCUUAGUGAUCUUCUAUUGGGUCUUUCUGAGGUUCAGAGAGGGUAAGUAACUUCCUCCAGGUCACACAGCAAGUCUGUGGGUGGCAGAAGCAAGCUAGCGCUGGGCAUUCAGUACAUACCACGAUGUGCUCCCUCUCUUGAUGCUUGGCCCCUGGGGCCUUCAGGGCUUUGGGACAUCUUGUCCUCAACCCUCUCCCUAGAUCAGUCUGUGAGGGUCCCUGUAGAUAUUGUGUACACCAUGCCCAUGUAUAUACAAGUACACACAGAUGUACACACAGAUGUACACAUGCUCCAGCCCCAGCUCUGCAUACCUGCACCUGCACCCCAGCCUUGGCCCCUGCCUGCGUCUGUGCUCAAAGCAGCAGCUCCAACCCUGCCUCUGUCCCCUUCCCCACCCACUGCCUGAGCCUUCUGAGCAGACCAGGUACCUUGGCUGCACCGGUGUGUGGCCCGCUCUCACCCAGGCACAGCCCCGCCACCAUGGAUCUCCGUGUACACUAUCAAUAAAAGUGGGUUUGUUACAAA